GAGUAGUACUGCCGGUUGGUCAGGGUUCGGCCUCAACAUGGCGGUUCCGGCCGGGCAGUGACCAAGGUUUUGCCGUCCGAAGGACUAAGUGGUGACUGUCGGCGUCUCCACCUAUCGGGGUGGAAUGCGAGCACGCGGGGACGAGCGCUGAGAAGCGGCGGUGACGGGAAGGGGGGGGUCAGUGGAUUGUGCCCCAGAAACCGAAGCGGCGGCGUCUGUUCCUUCUUGUUUCUAGGCUCCAGUGCGUUCGGGGCCCCGCCCGGCCGGGCCAGGCCGGCGGGCGGCGGCGGUAGCUGCUGCAGCCGCAGGAUAACCUCGCAGGGUGGGCCGGAGGGCGGGCGCCGCCGCUGCCUGUGCUGCGGCGAUGGCCCAGUGUGUACAAUCAGUGCAGGAGCUAAUCCCGGACUCCUUCGUCCCCUGUGUCGCUGCGCUGUGCAGCGACGAAGCCGAGCGGCUCACUCGUCUCAAUCACCUCAGCUUCGCGGAGCUGCUUAAGCCCUUCUCCCGCCUCACUUCCGAGGUUCACAUGAGAGAUCCUAAUAAUCAACUUCACGUAAUUAAAAAUUUGAAGAUAGCAGUAAGCAACAUUGUCACCCAGCCACCUCAGCCUGGAGCCAUCCGGAAGCUUUUGAAUGAUGUUGUUUCUGGCAGUCAGCCUGCAGAAGGAUUAGUAGCUAAUGUGAUUACAGCAGGAGAUUAUGACCUUAACAUCAGUGCCACUACUCCAUGGUUUGAGUCUUACAGAGAAACCUUUCUUCAGUCGAUGCCAGCAUUGGAUCAUGAAUUUCUGAACCACUAUUUAGCAUGUAUGUUGGUAGCGUCAUCUAGUGAAGCUGAACCUGUGGAACAGUUUUCAAAGUUGUCACAAGAACAGCAUCGAAUUCAGCACAACAGUGAUUAUUCCUACCCCAAGUGGUUUAUACCAAAUACACUUAAAUACUAUGUACUUUUACAUGAUGUAAGUGCAGGAGAUGAACAGAGAGCUGAAUCAAUUUAUGAAGAAAUGAAACAGAAAUAUGGAACUCAGGGUUGCUAUUUACUUAAAAUUAAUUCUCGAACAUCUAAUCGAGCAUCAGAUGAACAGAUACCAGAUCCUUGGAGUCAGUAUCUCCAGAAAAAUAGUAUUCAAAACCAGGAAUCAUAUGAAGAUGGCCCUUGUACUAUAACUUCAAAUAAGAAUUCUGAUAAUAACUUGCUUUCAUUGGAUGGAUUAGAUAACGAAGUCAAAGUAGAUGGCUUACCAAAUAACUUUAGAGCUCACCCACUUCAGUUGGAGCAAUCCAGUGACCCUUCUAACAGUAUUGAUGGCCCAGAUCAUCUAAGAUCUGCUUCAUCGUUACAUGAAACAAAGAAAGGAAAUACUGGAAUAAUUCAUGGUGCAUGUUUAACACUUACUGAUCAUGAUAGAAUUCGACAGUUUAUACAAGAGUUCACAUUUCGGGGCCUUUUGCCACAUAUAGAGAAAACAAUUAGGCAAUUAAACGAUCAGCUAAUAUCAAGAAAAGGUUUGAGUCGAUCUCUAUUUUCUGCAACUAAAAAAUGGUUUAGUGGCAGUAAAGUUCCAGAAAAGAGCAUUAAUGACCUGAAAAAUACAUCUGGCUUGCUGUAUCCGCCGGAAGCACCAGAACUUCAAAUCAGGAAAAUGGCUGACUUAUGUUUUUUGGUGCAGCAUUAUGAUUUGGCUUACAGUUGCUAUCAUACUGCAAAGAAAGAUUUUCUUAAUGAUCAAGCAAUGCUUUAUGCAGCUGGUGCCUUGGAAAUGGCAGCAGUGUCUGCUUUUCUUCAACCAGGAGCACCUAGGCCAUAUCCUGCUCAUUACAUGGAUACAGCAAUUCAGACAUACAGAGAUAUCUGCAAGAAUAUGGUGUUGGCUGAAAGAUGUGUGUUGCUUAGUGCUGAACUUUUAAAAAGCCAAAGCAAAUAUUCAGAGGCUGCAGCUCUCCUAAUACGGUUGACCAGUGAGGAUUCUGAUCUUCGAAGUGCACUUCUUUUGGAACAGGCAGCACAUUGCUUUAUAAACAUGAAAAGUCCCAUGGUUAGAAAAUAUGCAUUUCAUAUGAUAUUGGCAGGCCAUCGAUUUAGUAAAGCAGGGCAGAAAAAGCAUGCUUUACGCUGUUAUUGUCAAGCCAUGCAAGUUUACAAAGGAAAAGGCUGGUCUCUUGCAGAGGAUCACAUUAAUUUCACUAUUGGGCGCCAGUCCUAUACUCUUAGACAGCUGGAUAAUGCUGUGUCUGCUUUUAGGCAUAUUCUAAUUAAUGAAAGUAAACAAUCUGCUGCUCAACAGGGGGCUUUCCUCAGAGAAUAUCUUUAUGUUUACAAGAAUGUAAGUCAGCUGUCACCAGAUGGUCCUUUGCCACAGCUUCCUUUACCGUAUAUUAACAGUUCAGCAACACGGGUUUUUUUUGGCCAUGACAGACGACCAGCGGAUGGUGAAAAACAAGCAGCUACUCAUGUAAGUCUUGAUCAAGAAUAUGAUUCUGAAUCCUCUCAGCAGUGGCGAGAACUUGAGGAACAAGUUGUUUCUGUGGUUAACAAAGGAGUAAUUCCAUCCAAUUUUCAUCCCACACAAUACUGUUUGAACAGUUACUCAGAUAAUUCAAGAUUUCCACUUGCAGUUGUAGAAGAACCAAUUACAGUGGAAGUGGCUUUUAGAAACCCUUUGAAAGUUCUACUUUUGUUGACUGAUUUGUCAUUGCUUUGGAAGUUUCAUCCUAAAGAUUUCAGUGGAAAGGAUAAUGAAGAAGUUAAACAACUAGUUACAAGUGAACCUGAAAUGAUUGGAGCUGAAGUUAUUUCAGAGUUCUUAAUUAAUGGCGAAGAAUCAAAAGUGGCAAGACUAAAGCUCUUUCCCCAUCACAUAGGGGAGCUGCAUAUUCUGGGAGUUGUUUAUAAUCUUGGCACUAUUCAGGGCUCUAUGACAGUAGAUGGCAUUGGUGCUCUUCCCGGAUGUCACACAGGAAAAUAUUCCUUGAGUAUGUCAGUCCGAGGGAAGCAGGAUUUAGAAAUUCAAGGUCCUCGACUUAACAACACAAAAGAAGAGAAAACAUCUGUUAAAUAUGGCCCUGAUCGACGUUUAGAUCCCAUAAUCACAGAAGAAAUGCCACUGUUGGAGGUGUUCUUUAUACAUUUUCCUACAGGGCUUCUCUGUGGAGAAAUCCGAAAAGCAUAUGUAGAAUUUGUCAAUGUCAGCAAAUGUCCACUUACUGGAUUGAAGGUUGUUUCUAAACGUCCAGAGUUCUUUACUUUCGGUGGUAAUACUGCUGUUCUAACACCACUAAGUCCCUCAGCUUCUGAGAAUUGUAGUGCUUACAAGACUGUUGUGACAGAUGCUACCUCUGUGUGUACAGCACUCAUAUCAUCAGCUUCUUCUGUAGACUUUGGCAUUGGCACAGGAAGUCAACCAGAGGUGAUUCCUGUUCCCCUUCCUGACACUGUUCUUCUACCCGGAGCCUCAGUGCAGCUGCCAAUGUGGUUACGUGGGCCUGAUGAAGAAGGUGUCCAUGAAAUUAACUUUUUGUUUUACUAUGAAAGUGUCAAAAAGCAGCCAAAAAUACGGCACAGAAUAUUAAGACACACUGCAAUUAUUUGUACCAGUCGGUCUUUAAAUGUACGGGCCACUGUCUGCAGAAGUAAUUCUCUUGAAAAUGAAGAAGGCAGAGGAGGCAAUAUGCUAGUCUUUGUGGAUGUGGAAAAUACCAAUACUAGUGAAGCAGGCGUUAAGGAAUUCCACAUAGUGCAAGUAUCAAGUAGUAGCAAACACUGGAAGUUACAGAAAUCUGUAAAUCUUUCUGAAAACAAAGAUACCAAACUUGCCAGUAGGGAGAAGGGAAAGUUUUGCUUUAAGGCAAUAAGAUGUGAGAAAGAAGAAGCGGCCACACAGUCCUCUGAAAAAUAUACCUUUGCAGAUAUCAUCUUUGGAAAUGAACAGAUAAUAAGUUCAGCAAGCCCAUGUGCAGACUUCUUUUAUCGAAGUUUAUCUUCUGAAUUGAAAAAACCACAAGCUCACUUGCCUGUGCAUACAGAAAAACAGUCAACAGAGGAUGCUGUGAGAUUGAUUCAAAAAUGCAGUGAGGUAGAUUUGAAUAUUGUCAUAUUAUGGAAGGCAUACGUUGUGGAAGACAGUAAACAGCUUAUUUUGGAAGGUCAACAUCAUGUUAUUCUUCGCACUAUAGGAAAAGAAGCCUUUUCAUAUCCUCAGAAACAGGAGCCACCAGAAAUGGAACUAUUGAAAUUUUUCAGGCCAGAAAACAUUACAGUUUCCUCAAGGCCAUCAGUAGAGCAGCUUUCUAGUCUCAUUAAAACGAGUCUUCACUACCCAGAAUCAUUUAAUCAUCCAUUUCAUCAAAAAAGAUGUAUGCAGGGUUCACCUGGGGAAAUGUAAGAAAUACUGAAGGAUGGGCCGGGCGCGGUGGCUCACGCCUGUAAUCCCAGCACUUUGGGAGGCCAAGGCGGGCGGAUCACGAGGUCAGGAGAUCAAGACCAUCCUGGCUAACACGGUGAAACCCCAUCUCUACUAAAAAUACAAAAAAAUUAGCCGGGUGUGGUGGCGGGCACCUGUAGUCCCAGCUACUUGGGAGGCUGAGGCAGGAGAAUGGCAUGAACCCAGGAGGCGGAGCUUGCAGUGAGCCGAGAUCGUGCCACUGCAGUCCAGCCUGGGCGACAGAGCGAGACUCUGUCUCAAAAAAAAAAAAAAAAAAAAAGACUGAAAGAUGCUUCAUUCAGUCCUACCCCCAGAGGUUCCAGUUUGAUUGGCCCAGAGUAGGGGUUGGCAUCUGGAUUUUCUUAAGUUCUCCAGGUGAUCCUAAUAUGCAACCAUAAGUGAAAAUAAAAAUGUUUGUGUUUUAUCCUUAUUGAACCUCACACACUUCUAUGAACAAUUUUGAUUCUGUGAUUCAUUUUAACCCAAUCUUCUACUUCAGCUCUGUUUAUUAAACCCGUCCUGCUUCAUGUACUUUCUGAAUAACCUUGGUGCUUCUUUUUAACCUUAGUGGUUAAACCUUUGCUGCAUUGAGAGGCUAGGAUGUUUAGGAGUUCUCUACAUCAUUCUACUUAGGGGUUAAAAAACCCUAUGGAAUCUAUGUGAAACAGGAAAGUUUUGAUCAAACUAAAGUAGAAGAGUGGGUUAAAUGAAGCAUUCCAAAAUCAAAACUCUGCAUGGAAGUAUGUGAAAACAAGGCAGGUUCAAGGAUAAAAUGUGGCAGUUUUCUCCUUGGCUGCAUGUUAGAAUCAUUUGGGAAUUUCUGACAUUUCCAAUGCUUGGGCUGAUUCAAUCAGAUUCUCUGGAAGCAGGGUACCGGCAUCUCUAGUUUUAAAAUGUCUGCAGAUCAUACCCAUGUCCAUCUCUAUUAGUCAUUGUUGCCACAAUAAUGCUUCAUAACAAACCAUUUCAGAAAUGAGUAGCUUAUAACAAAGCAUUUAUUUCCAUACUCAUGGGUCUGCCAGUUGAUAAUUUGGCCGAAGCUGUGCUUUGGUCUGUGUGCUGUUUGGAUUUGGCACCUGAAGAAACUUGGGUUCCCGUCUGUGCCACAUAUAUUUUGGGCCCAGUCCAAAGGAGCAGCUGCUACCUGGAGUAUGUUCUGGUGGCAUGUCUCCGGAGUAUAAAAAGUGAGCCACAUUGCAAAAGCACAUUUAAGACUUUUGCUUGCAUCAAAAGAUGUUAAUAUUUCAUUGACCAAAUAGCCUCACUUCCAUAUCAACAAGGAUGAUUCACAGUCCCACAGAGAGAGUGAAUAACUGCUAAGCAGUACUCACAGUUACCACAGUAACCAAGGUUGAGAACCAUUGAAAUGAAGGAUCAAGUGACUGGGUGUCUGUGUAAAACUCAAAAACAGAUGAGAGAGUAUAAUUGAGAAAGCUAGAGAGUUGGGAGAUGGUGGUCAAAGUGGGGUGACCGAGUAUUAUGUUAGGGAUAGUUGUCUAAUGUGAUGGGAAAAAAUUUCAUGGUUUGGUCAUGGAAGUUGUGUGGCUGAGUUUUGAAUAGUACUGAAGAUUAUGGAGAUGAUAGGUCCAGGAUUUGGGAAGGUGCUGAAUAAGUCAUAUACCUAGACAGUGAAGUUGUCCAAAAUGAUGACAAGACUUGGAGUUGAAGGAAGAAAACAAACUUCCCUGACACUUUUAAAAUUAUGCCAAUAGAUAGUACAGAGGAGGGUAGCGAGAGAAUAGUGUCUUACUAGGUGUAUGCCUCUGCUUGACCGAUACAGCAGAUGAAUUCACAAAUGGGAGGUAAAGCAGAUGUUCAGACUACACAUGCUUCAUCUUUACCUCAAAUAUUUCAGAAUAUCCAUUUCUUCCCCUUUCCCCCAAAGAAUUCUCGCUGUACUGAGUUACUGUCACUGUGUUUGUUAGAAUGGGAACAGAAAAAAGAAUACAAACCUUAAGGUAGUUUAUGAUGAAAAAGUGGAGGCAUCUUUACAGGAGAGGUAGUAGAAAGAAAUCAUUAAGAACUACAUCAGCCACCCUGAGGUAUGGAAGAUGUUGGAAGAAAUACAGCAUCUAUUGUUGAGAGGACAAUACAGUUAAAGAUAGAUGUAGAAACACAAAGAGAAGAGAUGGAGGAUAUAAGGAAGCAUUCUUAAUUUAAUGGGGGUUUCAGAAAACAAGUAGAAAUGUGAGGAAAUGGGACAGUAGGAGGUUUGGUCAUGGUAGUGGGACACAGAGCAGUAGAGGUAUGAGAAUAGAAGAAAGAAUAGGUGACAGGAGAUAACAAAGAUAAAAUCAUACUAUGUUUAGCUGCCAUGAGCAUAAAUUGUUAUAUUAAAUAAUGUUUAUGGAGCUUUUGAACAUGUGCUAGUCACCAUUCUCAGCACUUAACAUGUUUUACCUAAUCACAACAAACCCAAGAGGUAGAAUCAAUUAUUAUUCUUUGCAGUUUACAGUUGAGAAAACUGAGGUACAGGUAGCAGUCUGACUCUAGAGCCCAGCUUUUUCACUGGAUGCAGUGGUGGGAGAAUAGUUGUCAGAACUUUGAUUUCUCAGCCCUGUUUGUGGUUCAUUAGAUUAGCAUUUUAGAAAAACUAAUGUGUAAAGCAGUUUUCAAAAUGUGGUCCCAAGACUGGACCUGGUGGCACACACCUGUAAUCCCAGCACUUUGGGAGGCCAAGGCGGGCGGAUCUCCUGAGGUCAGGAGUUCAAGACCAGCCUAGUCAACAUGGUGAAACCCCAUCUCUACUAAAAAAUAAAAAAAAAUUAGCCGGGUGUGGUGGCGAGCGCUUGUAAUCCCAGCUACUGGGGAGGCUGAGGCAGAAUAGCUUGAACCUGGGAAGCUGAGGGUGCAGUGAGCCAAGAUCGUGCCACUGCACUCCAGCCUGGGCAAAAAGAGCAAAACUCCAUCUCAAAGAAUAAAAAACAACAACAACAACAACAACAACAACCAAAAUGUGAUCCCAGACCAGGAGCAUUAGUAUUAGUAUCAUCUGGGAACUUAGAAAUGUAAUUUCUGUUUUUUGUUUUUUUUUUUUGAGACGGAGUCUUGCUCUGUCACCCAGGCUCGAGUGCAGUGGUGUGAUCUCGGCUCACUGCAAGCUCCACCUCCUGGGUUCAUGCCAUUCUUCUGCCUCAGCCUCCCGAGUAACUGGGACUAUAGGCACCUGCCACCACGCCCGGCUACUUUUUGUAUUUUUAGUAAAGACGGGGUUUCACCAUGUUAGCCAGGAUGAUCUUGAUCUCCUGACCUUGUGAUCCGCCCGCCUCGGUCUCCCAAAAUGCUGGGAUUACAAGCGCAAGCCACCGUGCCCAGCCUAGGAAUGCAAUGUUUGGGCCACACUCCAGACCUAUGGAAUCAGAAUCUCUGAGAGUAGGCCCAGCAGGUUUUUUAAAACAAGCUUGCCAGGUAUUUCUGGUGCAUACUCAAGUGUGAGAAACAUGGUUAAAGAAUAGAUUGCAUUGUGGUGCUAAUUAAGAGGCUCUUGCAGUAAAAUGAGACAUGAGACUUGAACUUGUAAGGAAAAUGAGAUACAGUGAAGUAACCAGGUUCCAGAGAUGUGUGGGUGAGAGAAUUGGCAGGAAUUUGUGAAGAACAUUGGGAGUGGAGGUUAGUGACUGUUAGGAGGAAUCAGUAUGAUACUUACAGUUUGCUGGGGUAGAUGGGGGUGCUCUUCACUGGAAUGAAGAUGAUGAGUUUCACUUUGGACCAGGAGAUAUCCACAUGUUCACAUUUCUUCUUCUACUAGAAGCAUUUGUAUAAGGUACAAAGAAUUUGACAUUUGAGGAUCAAAUGGGAACAGAAUAGCAUAAGUUCCUGAAUUUUUACUUUGGGCUACAAAUUAUGCAAUUGGAACUUAAUUUAAUGAGAUGCUUCAGACUGACUGGACACCUACCCAGUAGUCUUUGUUGCCCUUCUUGCCACAUGAGAAGUUUGUGGGGGAAGUUAGGGCAUAGCACCAGUACAACCUGGUAUGUAUUUUAAAUCAUCUUAGUUUUUGUUUAGGGAAACCUGUGACGUUUGCGGUAUUGUUUAAAAAGUAUUUCUCAGUAAGAAGAUAUAAAGUUUCUGAAAGUAUAAAAUAUAUUAUCUGAGCAGAAUUUAAAAGUUAAUGUGUAUGAACUUAUACGGUUACUAUUUUUUCUUCUUUACUAUCUUUGUGUUUAUAGAGUAAAAGGUAGAUAAUAGUAUAUAACCCUGCUUCAUUUGUACAUGUUAUAUUCAUUUCUUGCAUUCUUGAUUUGAAAUCUGUACCACUCUAUUCGCAUGUCCUCUUCUAUCACUGCCUUUUUUCCUAUGCUUUAGUAAUUUAUUAAUUAUGGUAUCAGAAACUAGGCUACCUGAGCAAAAUGUAUCCACUCGAAAGAGAUUUCCUCAUAACUAUAUAGAAAUCAUUCUUAUAUUCUUCAAAACAUGAUGUUGUGCAAAUUUGAUAGAAAAACAAAUGUCAGUCUAGGCCAAGUUCUCAAAAUUAAGUAAUUUUUAAUAAGCACAAAGACAACAGUAUUAGUUGUUGGCAUUUUCAUGGUUUACUUUUUCUUCAUUGAUCUAAGUUGAGAUUUUGUUUUUCAUUUUGUGAAAUAUCUAGAAACAUUUUAGUUGUUUUUAGAAGAUUAAUAAAUGAAAAUAAAAUAGUUCUGUGAAUGUAUAUAUUCUGAUAUUUAAUAUUGUCAUUGUAUUAAUAUAUUUUUUAUUUACAAUAUAAUUUGUCUUGAGUGAUUUUGGAA